AGCUUUCUCUUCUGUAGCAAUGAUAGUCAUAGCUACAUUCAGACUGUUUUCCUAAUUGAUGUAGUAGAUGAGGGAAGUGUAGGCAUUUAUGUUGGUGAUUUCAAGGUGAUCAAAAUCAGAGAUCAGAUCAGUCUGUGCAUGAUGAGGGCAUCAGCUAGGAAGACAAUAUACAGGGAAUGUGGACAGAUACAGGAAGGACAGAGUGAAAGGCAUUGUUUGAGUACUGCUUAAGUACUAGAGACAUGGUCUCACUUCAUUGCCCAGGCUAGUCUCGAACUUCUGGGCUCCAGAGAUCCACCCACCUUGGCCUCCCAAAGUGUCAGGAUUACAGGUGUGAGCCAUGGCACCCGACCCAGGAAGAAGAAAAUUAACCCAGAAAAAUUCCUACCUUUUCCUUGCUUGCAUCUGGUAAUAGGAAAUGAAUGAUGAUGGAAAAGUCAAUGCUAGCUCUGAGGGGUACUUUAUUUUAGUUGGAUUUUCUAAUUGGCCUCAUCUGGAAGUAGUUAUCUUUGUGGUUGUCUUGAUCUUCUACUUGAUGACACUGAUAGGAAACCUGUUCAUCAUCAUCCUGUCAUACCUGGACUCCCAUCUGCACACACCAAUGUACUUCUUCCUUUCAAACCUCUCAUUUCUGGAUCUCUGCUACACCACCAGCUCUAUCCCUCAGUUGCUGGUCAAUCUCUGGGGCCCGGAAAAGACCAUCUCUUAUGCUGGUUGCAUGAUUCAACUUUACUUUGUUCUCGCACUGGGAACCACAGAGUGUGUCCUACUGGUGGUGAUGUCCUAUGACCGUUAUGCAGCUGUGUGUAGACCUUUGCAUUACACUGUCCUCAUGCACCCUCGUUUCUGCCACCUGCUGGCUGUGGCUUCUUGGGUAAGUGGUUUUACCAACUCAGCACUUCAUUCCUCCUUCACCUUCUGGGUACCUCUGUGUGGACACCGCCAAGUAGAUCACUUUUUCUGUGAAGUUCCAGCACUUCUGCGAUUAUCGUGUGUUGAUACCCAUGUCAAUGAGCUGACCCUCAUGAUCACAAGCUCCAUAUUUGUUCUCAUACCUCUCAUCCUCAUUCUCACUUCUUAUGGUGCCAUCGUCCAAGCUGUACUGAGGAUGCAGUCAACCACUGGGCUUCAGAAAGUGUUUGGAACAUGUGGAGCUCAUCUUAUGGCUGUAUCUCUCUUUUUCAUUCCGGCC